AGUGGCGUCGGAACUGCAAAGCACCUGUGAGCUUGCGGAAGUCAGUUCAGACUCCAGCCCGCUCCAGCCCGGCCCGACCCGACCGCACCCGGCGCCUGCCCUCGCUCGGCGUCCCCGGCCAGCCAUGGGCCCUUGGAGCCGCAGCCUCUCGGCGCUGCUGCUGCUGCUGCAGGUCUCCUCUUGGCUCUGCCAGGAGCCGGAGCCCUGCCACCCUGGCUUUGACGCCGAGAGCUACACGUUCACGGUGCCCCGGCGCCACCUGGAGAGAGGCCGCGUCCUGGGCAGAGUGAAUUUUGAAGAUUGCACCGGUCGACAAAGGACAGCCUAUUUUUCCCUCGACACCCGAUUCAAAGUGGGCACAGAUGGUGUGAUUACAGUCAAAAGGCCUCUACGGUUUCAUAACCCACAGAUCCAUUUCUUGGUCUACGCCUGGGACUCCACCUACAGAAAGUUUUCCACCAAAGUCACGCUGAAUACAGUGGGGCACCACCACCGCCCCCCGCCCCAUCAGGCCUCCGUUUCUGGAAUCCAAGCAGAAUUGCUCACAUUUCCCAACUCCUCUCCUGGCCUCAGAAGACAGAAGAGAGACUGGGUUAUUCCUCCCAUCAGCUGCCCAGAAAAUGAAAAAGGCCCAUUUCCUAAAAACCUGGUUCAGAUCAAAUCCAACAAAGACAAAGAAGGCAAGGUUUUCUACAGCAUCACUGGCCAAGGAGCUGACACACCCCCUGUUGGUGUCUUUAUUAUUGAAAGAGAAACAGGAUGGCUGAAGGUGACAGAGCCUCUGGAUAGAGAACGCAUUGCCACAUACACUCUCUUCUCUCACGCUGUGUCAUCCAACGGGAAUGCAGUUGAGGAUCCAAUGGAGAUUUUGAUCACGGUAACCGAUCAGAAUGACAACAAGCCCGAAUUCACCCAGGAGGUCUUUAAGGGGUCUGUCAUGGAAGGUGCUCUUCCAGGAACCUCUGUGAUGGAGGUCACAGCCACAGACGCGGACGAUGAUGUGAACACCUACAAUGCCGCCAUCGCUUACACCAUCCUCAGCCAAGAUCCUGAGCUCCCUGACAAAAAUAUGUUCACCAUUAACAGGAACACAGGAGUCAUCAGUGUGGUCACCACUGGGCUGGACCGAGAGAGUUUCCCUACGUAUACCCUGGUGGUUCAAGCUGCUGACCUUCAAGGUGAGGGGUUAAGCACAACAGCAACAGCUGUGAUCACAGUCACUGACACCAACGAUAAUCCUCCGAUCUUCAAUCCCACCACGUACAAGGGUCAGGUGCCUGAGAACGAGGCUAACGUCGUAAUCACCACACUGAAAGUGACUGAUGCUGAUGCCCCCAAUACCCCAGCGUGGGAGGCUGUAUACACCAUAUUGAAUGAUGAUGGUGGACAAUUUGUCGUCACCACAAAUCCAGUGAACAACGAUGGCAUUUUGAAAACAGCAAAGGUUUGUAUGGUACCUGGCAAGAUGCAGAAACUGGCAUCCUCACAGCUGUUCAUACCCUUGUCCCCUGGGCUUGGAUUUUGAGGCCAAGCAGCAGUACAUUCUACACGUAGCAGUGACGAAUGUGGUACCUUUUGAGGUCUCUCUCACCACCUCCACAGCCACCGUCACCGUGGAUGUGCUGGAUGUGAAUGAAGCCCCCAUCUUUGUGCCUCCUGAAAAGAGAGUGGAAGUGUCCGAGGACUUUGGCGUGGGCCAGGAAAUCACAUCCUACACUGCCCAGGAGCCAGACACAUUUAUGGAACAGAAAAUAACAUAUCGGAUUUGGAGAGACACUGCCAACUGGCUGGAGAUUAAUCCGGACACUGGUGCCAUUUCCACUCGGGCUGAGCUGGACAGGGAGGAUUUUGAGCACGUGAAGAACAGCACGUACACAGCCCUAAUCAUAGCUACAGACAAUGGUUCUCCAGUUGCUACUGGAACAGGGACACUUCUGCUGAUCCUGUCUGAUGUGAAUGACAACGCCCCCAUACCAGAACCUCGAACUAUAUUCUUCUGUGAGAGGAAUCCAAAGCCUCAGGUCAUAAACAUCAUUGAUGCAGACCUUCCUCCCAAUACAUCUCCCUUCACAGCAGAACUAACACACGGGGCGAGUGCCAACUGGACCAUUCAGUACAACGACCCAACCCAAGAAUCUAUCAUUUUGAAGCCAAAGAUGGCCUUAGAGGUGGGUGACUACAAAAUCAAUCUCAAGCUCAUGGAUAACCAGAAUAAAGACCAAGUGACCACCUUAGAGGUCAGCGUGUGUGACUGUGAAGGGGCCGCUGGCGUCUGUAGGAAGGCACAGCCUGUCGAAGCAGGAUUGCAAAUUCCUGCCAUUCUGGGGAUUCUUGGAGGAAUUCUUGCUUUGCUAAUUCUGAUUCUGCUGCUCUUGCUGUUUCUUCGGAGGAGAGCGGUGGUCAAAGAGCCCUUACUGCCCCCAGAGGAUGACACCCGGGACAACGUUUAUUACUAUGAUGAAGAAGGAGGCGGAGAAGAGGACCAGGACUUUGACUUGAGCCAGCUGCACAGGGGCCUGGACGCUCGGCCUGAAGUGACUCGUAACGACGUUGCACCAACCCUCAUGAGUGUCCCCCGGUAUCUUCCCCGCCCUGCCAAUCCCGAUGAAAUUGGAAAUUUUAUUGAUGAAAAUCUGAAAGCGGCUGAUACUGACCCCACAGCCCCGCCUUAUGAUUCUCUGCUCGUGUUUGACUAUGAAGGAAGCGGUUCCGAAGCUGCUAGUCUGAGCUCCCUGAACUCCUCAGAGUCAGACAAAGACCAGGACUAUGACUACUUGAACGAAUGGGGCAAUCGCUUCAAGAAGCUGGCUGACAUGUACGGAGGCGGCGAGGACGACUAGGGGACUCGAGAGAGGCGGGCCCCAGACCCAUGUGCUGGGAAAUGCAGAAAUCACGUUGCUGGUGGUUUUUCAGCUCCCUUCCCUUGAGAUGAGUUUCUGGGGAAAAAAAAGAGACUGGUUAGUGAUGCAGUUAGUAUAGCUUUAUACUCUCUCCACUUUAUAGCUCUAAUAAGUUUGUGUUAGAAAAGUUUCGACUUAUUUCUUAAAGCUUUUUUUUUUUUCCCAUCACUCUUUACAUGGUGGUGAUGUCCAAAAGAUACCCAAAUUUUAAUAUUCCAGAAGAACAACUUUAGCAUCAGAAGGUUCACCCAGCACCUUGCAGAUUUUCUUAAGGAAUUUUGUCUCACUUUUAAAAAGAAGGGGAGAAGUCAGCUACUCUAGUUCUGUUGUUUUGUGUAUAUAAUUUUUUAAAAAAAAUUUGUGUGCUUCUGCUCAUUACUACACUGGUGUGUCCCUCUGCCUUUUUUUUUUUUUUAAGACAGGGUCUCAUUCUAUCGGCCAGGCUGGAGUGCAGUGGUGCAAUCACAGCUCACUGCAGCCUUGUCCUCCCAGGCUCAAGCUAUCCUUGCACCUCAGCCUCCCAAGUAGCUGGGACCACAGGCAUGCACCACUACGCAUGACUAAUUUUUUAAAUAUUUGAGACGGGGUCUCCCUGUGUUACCCAGGCUGGUCUCAAACUCCUGGGCUCAAGUGAUCCUCCCAUCUUGGCCUCCCAGAGUAUUGGGAUUACAGACAUGAGCCACUGCACCUGCCCAGCUCCCCAACUCCCUGCCAUUUUUUAAGAGACAGUUUCGCUCCAUCGCCCAGGCCUGGGAUGCAGUGAUGUGAUCAUAGCUCACUGUAACCUCAAACUCUGGGGCUCAAGCAGUUCUCCCACCAGCCUCCUUUUUAUUUUUUUGUACAGAUGGGGUCUUGCUAUGUUGCCCAAGCUGGUCUUAAACUCCUGGCCUCAAGCAAUCCUUCUGCCUUGGCCCCCCAAAGUGCUGGGAUUGUGGGCAUGAGCUGCUGUGCCCAGCCUCCAUGUUUUAAUAUCAACUCUCACUCCUGAAUUCAGUUGCUUUGCCCAAGAUAGGAGUUCUCUGAUGCAGAAAUUAUUGGGCUCUUUUAGGGUAAGAAGUUUGUGUCUUUGUCUGGCCACAUCUUGACUAGGUAUUGUCUACUCUGAAGACCUUUAAUGGCUUCCCUCUUUCAUCUCCUGAGUAUGUAACUUGCAAUGGGCAGCUAUCCAGUGACUUGUUCUGAGUAAGUGUGUUCAUUAAUGUUUAUUUAGCUCUGAAGCAAGAGUGAUAUACUCCAGGACUUAGAAUAGUGCCUAAAGUGCUGCAGCCAAAGACAGAGCGGAACUAUGAAAAGUGGGCUUGGAGAUGGCAGGAGAGCUUGUCAUUGAGCCUGGCAAUUUAGCAAACUGAUGCUGAGGAUGAUUGAGGUGGGUCUACCUCAUCUCUGAAAAUUCUGGAAGGAAUGGAGGAGUCUCAACAUGUGUUUCUGACACAAGAUCCGUGGUUUGUACUCAAAGCCCAGAAUCCCCAAGUGCCUGCUUUUGAUGAUGUCUACAGAAAAUGCUGGCUGAGCUGAACACAUUUGCCCAAUUCCAGGUGUGCACAGAAAACCGAGAAUAUUCAAAAUUCCAAAUUUUUUUCUUAGGAGCAAGAAGAAAAUGUGGCCCUAAAGGGGGUUAGUUGAGGGGUAGGGGGUAGUGAGGAUCUUGAUUUGGAUCUCUUUUUAUUUAAAUGUGAAUUUCAACUUUUGACAAUCAAAGAAAAGACUUUUGUUGAAAUAGCUUUACUGUUUCUCAAGUGUUUUGGAGAAAAAAAUCAACCCUGCAAUCACUUUUUGGAAUUGUCUUGAUUUUUCGGCAGUUCAAGCUAUAUCGAAUAUAGUUCUGUGUAGAGAAUGUCACUGUAGUUUUGAGUGUAUACAUGUGUGGGUGCUGAUAAUUGUGUAUUUUCUUUGGGGGUGGAAAAGGAAAACAAUUCAAGCUGAGAAAAGUAUUCUCAAAGAUGCAUUUUUAUAAAUUUUAUUAAACAAUUUUGUUAAA